AGUCCUCGCUUCCCUGGGAGGGGGAAGGUAAGUGCGCGCAGUCCAUCCGGCGAAGAGCAGGUCAGCCUACGGAGGGCUCAGCCUACGGAGGGGCUCAGCCGACACAGGCUCUUCCUUCUGCCCAGCUCCGUCCCACCCAGCAGCCCGCAGAGAAAGGAGGCAGCUGGCACCACACUGGGCUUUGGAGACACUGCGGGGACUGUGGACCCCACCCUGCUGCACGGAGCUCCUGCAAAAGCAAACCUGAGAACCUUGGGUCCUCCCAGCGCCCAGCCAUGGGGGAACUGUGCCGCAGGGACUCCGCACUCACGGCACUGGACGAGGAGACACUGUGGGAGAUGAUGGAGAGCCACCGCCACAGGAUCGUACGCUGCAUCUGCCCCAGCCGCCUCACCCCCUACCUGCGCCAGGCCAAGGUGCUGUGCCAGCUGGACGAGGAGGAGGUGCUGCACAGCCCCCGGCUCACCAACAGCGCCAUGCGGGCCGGGCACUUGCUGGAUUUGCUGAAGACUCGAGGGAAGAACGGGGCCAUCGCCUUCCUGGAGAGCCUGAAGUUCCACAACCCUGACGUCUACACCCUGGUCACCGGGCUGCAGCCUGAUGUUGACUUCAGUAACUUUAGCGGUCUCAUGGAGACAUCCAAGCUGACCGAGUGCCUGGCUGGGGCCAUCGGCAGCCUGCAGGAGGAGCUGAACCAGGAAAAGGGGCAGAAGGAGGUGCUGCUGCGGCGGUGCCAGCAGCUGCAGGAGCACCUGGGCCUGGCCGAGACCCGUGCCGAGGGCCUGCACCAGCUGGAGGCUGACCACAGCCGCAUGAAGCGUGAGGUUAGCGCACACUUCCAUGAGGUGCUGAGGCUGAAGGACGAGAUGCUCAGCCUCUCGCUGCACUAUAGCAAUGCGCUGCAGGAGAAGGAGCUGGCCGCCUCACGCUGCCGCAGCCUGCAGGAGGAGCUGUAUCUACUGAAGCAGGAGCUGCAGCGAGCCAACAUGGUUUCCUCCUGUGAGCUGGAAUUGCAAGAGCAGUCCCUGAGGACAGCCAGCGACCAGGAGUCCGGGGAUGAGGAGCUGAACCGCCUGAAGGAGGAGAAUGAGAAACUGCGCUCGCUGACUUUCAGCCUGGCGGAGAAGGACAUUCUGGAGCAGAGCCUGGACGAGGCGCGGGGGAGCCGACAGGAGCUGGUGGAGCGCAUCCACUCGCUGCGGGAGCGGGCCGUGGCUGCCGAGAGGCAGCGAGAGCAGUACUGGGAAGAGAAGGAACAGACCCUGCUGCAGUUCCAGAAGAGUAAGAUGGCCUGCCAACUCUACAGGGAGAAGGUGAAUGCGCUGCAGGCCCAGGUGUGCGAGCUGCAGAAGGAGCGAGACCAGGCGUACUCCGCGAGGGACAGUGCUCAGAGGGAGAUUUCCCAGAGCCUGGUGGAGAAGGACUCCCUCCGCAGGCAGGUGUUCGAGCUGACGGACCAGGUCUGCGAGCUGCGCACACAGCUUCGCCAGCUGCAGGCAGAGCCUCCGGGUGUGCUCAAGCAGGAAGCCAGGACCAGGGAGCCCUGUCCACGGGAGAAGCAGCGGCUGGUGCGGAUGCAUGCCAUCUGCCCCAGAGACGACAGCGACUGCAGCCUCGUCAGCUCCACAGAGUCUCAGCUCUUGUCGGACCUGAGUGCCACGUCCAGCCGCGAGCUGGUGGACAGCUUCCGCUCCAGCAGCCCCGCGCCCCCCAGCCAGCAGUCCCUGUACAAGCGGGUGGCCGAGGACUUCGGGGAAGAACCCUGGUCUUUCAGCAGCUGCCUGGAGAUCCCGGAGGGAGACCCGGGAGCCCUGCCGGGAGCUAAGGCAGGCGACCCACACCUGGAUUAUGAGCUCCUAGACACGGCAGACCUUCCGCAGCUGGAAAGCAGCCUGCAGCCAGUCUCCCCUGGAAGGCUUGAUGUCUCGGAGAGCGGCGUCCUCAUGCGGCGGAGGCCAGCCCGCAGGAUCCUGAGCCAGGUCACCAUGCUGGCGUUCCAGGGGGAUGCAUUGCUGGAGCAGAUCAGCGUCAUCGGCGGGAACCUCACGGGCAUCUUCAUCCACCGGGUCACCCCGGGCUCGGCGGCGGACCAGAUGGCCUUGCGCCCGGGCACCCAGAUUGUGAUGGUUGAUUACGAAGCCUCAGAGCCCUUGUUCAAGGCAGUCCUGGAGGACACGACCCUGGAGGAGGCCGUGGGGCUUCUCAGGAGGGUGGACGGCUUCUGCUGCCUGUCUGUGAAGGUCAACACGGACGGUUAUAAGAGGCUACUCCAGGACCUGGAGGCCAAAGUGGCGACCUCGGGGGACUCAUUCUACAUCCGGGUCAACCUGGCCAUGGAGGGCAGGGCCAAAGGGGAGCUGCAGGUGCAUUGCAACGAGGUCCUGCACGUCACCGACACCAUGUUCCAGGGCUGCGGCUGCUGGCAUGCCCACCGCGUGAACUCUUACACCAUGAAGGAUACUGCCGCGCACGGCACCAUCCCCAACUACUCCAGGGCUCAGCAGCAGCUCAUAGCCCUCAUCCAGGACAUGACUCAGCAGUGCACCGUGACCCGCAAGCCAUCUUCUGGGGGACCACAGAAGCUGGUCCGCAUCGUCAGUAUGGACAAAGCCAAGGCCAGCCCUCUGCGUUUGUCCUUUGACAGGGGCCAGUUGGACCCCAGCAGGAUGGAGGGCUCCAGCACGUGCUUCUGGGCCGAGAGCUGCCUCACCCUGGUGCCCUAUACCCUGGUGCGGCCCCAUCGACCCGCCCGGCCCCGGCCUGUGCUCCUCGUGCCCAGGGCGGUUGGGAAGAUCCUGAGCGAGAAACUGUGCCUCCUCCAAGGGUUUAAGAAGUGCCUGGCAGAGUACUUGAGCCAGGAGGAGUAUGAGGCCUGGAGCCAGAGAGGGGACAUCAUCCAGGAGGGAGAGGUGUCCGGGGGCCGCUGCUGGGUGACCCGCCAUGCUGUGGAGUCCCUCAUGGAAAAGAACACCCAUGCCCUCCUGGACGUCCAGCUGGACAGUGUCUGCACCCUGCACAGGAUGGACAUCUUCCCCAUCGUCAUCCACGUCUCUGUCAACGAGAAGAUGGCAAAGAAGCUCAAGUAGGUGCACGCUGGGGGCUGGGCAGGGGCUUCGAAGCGGCUCCUGGGCUCCCCCAAAGCCCACGGCAGGUGCCUCUGGAGUGUGCUCUGCGGUUUGCAGGAAGCUGAGGCGCUGACAGGGCCGUUUCCGCACAACUUUGGGACAAGGGCCCCGCUGAUUGCUCAUGAGAUUCCCCUGAUUUUGGCCGGGCGUGGUGGCUCACGCCUGUAAUCCCAGCACUUUGGGAGGCCAGGGUGGGCAGAUUGCUUGAGGUCAGCAGUUCGAGACCAGCCUGGCCAACAUGGAGAAACCCUGUCUCUAUUAAAAAUACAAAAACUAGCCAGGUGUGGCGGCGGGCGCCUGUAAUCCCAGCUACUCGGGAGGCUGAGACAUGAUAAUUACUUGAACUGGGAGGUGGAGUUGCGGUGAGCCAAGAUCGCGCCACUGCACUCCAGCCUGGGUGACAGAGCGAGACUCUGUCUCAACAAAACAAAACAACAACAACAACAACUGCUCUGAUUUCACGCUUACCAAACAAACUUGAUUUCAAAUCUGGCCUCUCCAGAAUCUUGAUACCAGGAUGACGGUGCCUUUUACAGUGGGCAAAAGUAGCCUAGUCACUGGAAAAUGACAUUUUAUAAUUGAAAUUUAAAGUUGUAAAUUAACAAAUUGGCACUCCCUCCCCCAAGAGCAGCUCAGAGGACCAUUGUAAGGCCAGAACCCCACCCGGCCUCAGCUCCACUGACCCUCCACUUACUGGUGCUUGGCUAGCACAAUCUAAUCCUUGUCGGCUAAGGACAAAAAAAAAAAAAGUAAAAAAAUUACUUGGUUUCCUGGGGACAGACCAAGAUGUCCUGCUACUGUGCCCUUUCUACUCCAGGAAGCAAGGCUGUGUUCUAGACAACCUGCCUCCCACCACUGGGGCCUGGGGCCUAUUUUCUUUACAAGGUCCCCUCAAAGCGAGGCCACCUGUGUUUAGGGGUGUUUGGGUGCAUGUCAUCACUACCCUAGCCAGGGCUCCUGGGCCCUUGCUCUCCCCUGAGCCCGCCCCCCCCAACUCUGGCCUGUGCAGGAAGGGCCUACAGCGGUUGGGCACCUCAGAGGAGCAGCUCCUGGAGGCUGCGAGGCAGGAGGAGGGAGACCUGGACCGGGCGCCCUGUCUAUACAGCAGCCUGGCUCCUGACGGCUGGAGCGACCUGGACGGCCUGCUCAGCUGUGUCCGCCAGGCCAUCGCCGACGAGCAGAAGAAGGUGGUGUGGACGGAGCAGAGCCCCCGAUGAUGCACCGUGCCCCUUCCCGGGACUGUGGGGGCUUCUGUGUGCCUGUUAAUGCAGUCCUGUUCCUCAGCCCAGGCCCUCUUGGCACAGCUGUGGGCUCCUUGGCACAUGAGGCCGGCUCUCCCCACUGGCUGGGGUCUAACCUUGAACCCUCACCACGUGCAGGUCACACACAGUGAAGCCACUUGUAACUGCACACUUUUCUGUGGAAACAUCUUCACCCUUUACCAGGCUUGGCAUGGUCUGAACUGGAAACCCUGAGAAUGUUUCUGCAGUGGGACAGGAGGGACGUCUUCCCAUGCCUUCCCUAGAACCGGAGGCCCCGGACUUCUCUGGAAAACCGCCUGUCUGCAGGCCCGAUUCAAAUCUAUGGGGGCUGCACUUCCCUUUUACAUUUUGAUGUGUCAAAGGCUUUUGGAGUGACCAAAAGCACAGAGGCAGCGGGUGGGGCGCCUGGGUGGUCCCCAAGGUCGCUGCCACCCUUGCCCGGGGCAGAGGCAGAAGCCCACAUAUGCUGUGACGCUGGCCACCUUUUCUCAGCUUCUGAGGCUGCGAUGCCUCAGGAACUCCAGUUUACAGAGACCAGUGUGUUUACUUGUAAAUAAAGCCUCUGCGUGGUGGAGACGGUACUUUCAGUGGGUCUGUGCCCCGUGGCCCCUGUGCCUGUUCGGUGGGGGUGUCCCAGAGAAGCCUGGCACCAGUACCCCCGUACAAGGCCCAGCGGACUCUGCCUUCCCCUGACCUGGCUUUGCACCCCAGCCCUUCUUGGGCCAAACAUCUUUACUCCACCUUCAGGGCUCGGGGAGGACCCAGGUCCGCCAGCACCUGGCCUUGCCCCUGCCUCCUGGGGCUGUUGCAGACUGAAUGUCAUUUUGACAGCAGUGUCCAAGAAUCAGGAAGCUGUUCUAGAAUUCAGGUUGGUAUCAUCAUAAAUGAGUUCAGAAAAAGAACUUCUGUAUAUUUUACUAAAAUAAAAAGCUUUUACAAUA